AGCACAGAGUUGGGAGUGACUCCAGAGCCUCCUGCAAGAUGCUGUUGAUUCUGCUGUCAGUGGCCCUGCUGGCCCUGAGCUCAGCUCAGAACUUAAAUGAAGAUGUCAGCCAGGAAGAAUCUCCCUCCCUAAUAGCAGGAAAUCCACAAGGAGCACCCCCACAAGGAGGCAACAAACCUCAAGGUCCCCCAUCUCCUCCAGGAAAGCCACAAGGACCACCCCCACAAGGAGGCAACCAGCCUCAAGGUCCCCCACCUCCUCCAGGAAAGCCACAAGGACCACCCCCACAAGGAGGCAACAAACCUCAAGGUCCCCCACCUCCAGGAAAGCCACAAGGACCACCCCCACAAGGAGACAAGUCCCGAAGUCCCCGAUCUCCUCCAGGAAAGCCACAAGGACCACCCCCACAAGGAGGCAACCAGCCUCAAGGUCCUCCACCUCCUCCAGGAAAGCCACAAGGACCACCCCCACAAGGAGGCAACAAACCUCAAGGUCCCCCACCUCCAGGAAAGCCACAAGGACCACCCCCACAAGGAGACAACAAGUCCCGAAGUUCUCGAUCUCCUCCAGGAAAGCCACAAGGACCACCCCCACAAGGAGGCAACCAGCCCCAAGGUCCCCCACCUCCUCCAGGAAAGCCACAAGGACCACCCCCACAAGGAGGCAACAAACCUCAAGGUCCCCCACCUCCAGGAAAGCCACAAGGACCACCCCCACAAGGAGACAACAAGUCCCGAAGUGCCCGAUCUCCUCCAGGAAAGCCACAAGGACCACCCCCACAAGGAGGCAACCAGCCUCAAGGUCCCCCACCUCCUCCAGGAAAGCCACAAGGACCACCCCCACAAGGAGGCAACAAACCUCAAGGUCCCCCACCUCCAGGAAAGCCACAAGGACCACCCCCACAAGGAGACAAGUCCCGAAGUCCCCGAUCUCCUCCAGGAAAGCCACAAGGACCACCCCCACAAGGAGGCAACCAGCCUCAAGGUCCUCCACCUCCUCCAGGAAAGCCACAAGGACCACCCCCACAAGGAGGCAACAAACCUCAAGGUCCCCCACCUCCAGGAAAGCCACAAGGACCACCCCCACAAGGAGACAACAAGUCCCGAAGUUCUCGAUCUCCUCCAGGAAAGCCACAAGGACCACCCCCACAAGGAGGCAACCAGCCCCAAGGUCCCCCACCUCCUCCAGGAAAGCCACAAGGACCACCCCCACAAGGAGGCAACAAACCUCAAGGUCCCCCACCUCCAGGAAAGCCACAAGGACCACCCCCACAAGGAGACAACAAGUCCCGAAGUGCCCGAUCUCCUCCAGGAAAGCCACAAGGACCACCCCCACAAGGAGGCAACCAGCCCCAAGGUCCCCCACCUCCUCCAGGAAAGCCACAAGGACCACCCCCACAAGGAGGCAACAAACCUCAAGGUCCCCCACCUCCAGGAAAGCCACAAGGACCACCCCCACAAGGAGGCAGCAAGUCCCGAAGUUCUCGAUCUCCUCCAGGAAAGCCACAAGGACCACCCCCACAAGGAGGCAACCAGCCUCAAGGUCCCCCACCUCCUCCAGGAAAGCCACAAGGACCACCCCCACAAGGAGGCAACAAACCUCAAGGUCCCCCACCUCCAGGAAAGCCACAAGGACCACCCCCACAAGGAGGCAGCAAGUCCCGAAGUGCCCGAUCUCCUCCAGGAAAGCCACAAGGACCACCCCAACAAGAAGGCAACAAUCCUCAAGGUCCCCCACCUCCAGCAGGAGGCAAUCCCCAGCAGCCUCAGGCACCUCCUGCUGGACAGCCCCAGGGACCACCACGCCCUCCUCAAGGGGGCAGACCUUCCAGACCUCCCCAGUGACAGCCUCCCCAGUCAUCUAGGAUUCAAUGACAGGAAGUGAAUAAGAAGAUGAGAGUGAUUCAAAUGAUUCAAAUUCCAUGACAUUGGAAAAAGGUCAUCAUAGCUCUAACUUCAAUAUACCAAUAAAAUAAUCAGCUUGCAA